GACAUUACAUUUCACUUGGUUACAGCUGACUGGGGAUUUUAAUCAUUUGGAGCCACACUGAAAAAAAAAUUUCCCCCUGCAAUCUACUCUUAACUGAUAGUCGCUAACUUUGGUUAUGUGUGGUAAGUAUUUGACAAUGUCUAUUCAGAAUAUUACAUUAAUUGAUUUCUCAAACAAAGGUCCUUUCUGAAAUGGUAUCUAUGAUUCAGCUAUUCAAAACCUAAUGAAGUUGGUGACUAUGACAAUGUGGAGAAAUCAUGACAGAAAAUGUGGUUUGUACUGGGGCUGUCAAUGCUGUAAAGGAAGUUUGGGAAAAAAGAAUAAAGAAACUCAAUGAAGACCUGAAGCGAGAGAAGGAAUUUCAACACAAGCUAGUGCGGAUCUGGGAAGAACGAGUAAGCUUAACCAAGCUAAGAGAAAAGGUCACCAGGGAAGAUGGAAGAGUCAUUUUGAAGAUAGAAAAAGAGGAAUGGAAGACCCUCCCUUCUUCUCUGCUGAAACUGAAUCAACUACAGGAAUGGCAACUUCAUAGAACUGGUUUGCUGAAAAUUCCUGAAUUCAUUGGAAGAUUCCAGAACCUCAUUGUGUUAGAUUUAUCUCGAAACACAAUUUCAGAGAUACCACCAGGGAUUGGACUGCUUACUAGACUUCAGGAACUGAUUCUCAGCUACAACAAAAUCAAGACUGUCCCCAAGGAACUAAGUAAUUGUGCCAGCUUGGAGAAACUAGAACUGGCUGUUAACAGAGAUAUAUGUGAUCUUCCACAAGAGCUCAGCAAUCUGCUAAAACUUACUCACCUUGAUCUGAGUAUGAACGAUUUUACUACAAUCCCUCUUGCUGUGUUGAACAUGCCUGCCCUUGAGUGGCUGGACAUGGGAAGCAACAAACUUGAACAACUUCCUGAUACUAUAGAAAGAAUGCAAAAUCUACAUACGUUAUGGCUGCAACGAAAUGAAAUAACAUGCUUGCCUCAAACAAUCAGCAAUAUGAAAAAUCUGGGUACUCUUGUUCUCAGCAACAAUAAACUGCAAGAUAUUCCAGUAUGCAUGGAAGAAAUGGCAAAUCUGAGGUUUGUCAACUUCAGAGACAACCCACUGAAAUUGAAAGUAUCACUUCCUCCCAGUGAAGGCACAGAUGAAGAAGAGGAACGGGAAUUAUUUGGCCUUCAGUUUAUGCACACAUACAUACAAGAGUCACGGAGAAGAGCAGCUCUUCAGUUUUGUGUUUGUCAUGGACAGAUUCUGACAAUAUAUACAUGUAUGGCUCUGGAAAUUUGAAGAUCACCAAGUCAACGGUUCAACUACUUUACCAAUCUCCAUAAAUACGGAUGGAUAAUAUAAUUCAAGAUGCCCUUCUAAAGAGGAUUACUUUGGUGAAUUCUCUAAUGUUUGGAUUUCUGAAGUAAAAAGAAAAGCUAUUACCAAAGUUUAAUGAGGCCACAGCAUUUUUUAAAGUUCAUAUUAUUUGCUAUUUAAAGUAUAUAUUUUUUUGAUAUAAAAAUAUAAUUAAAAAAUUUUUUUUGGUGGAAGACAGAUGAUGCUCAAAUUUCUUUUCCAUUAAGCAGUUGUUUCUGGUGAUGAAGAAUGAUUUGGUAAAGCAGUUAACAAAACAUUUUCCAAAGACACCAGAGGGUCUGUAUAGUACUGCAAAGCAGGACUGAAUCCCUUCUGCUGCAAAUACUGGAUUCGACCUUGGUCAAUCAGCAAUUUACAAAGAUGCCCUAUUUUCUUCUUUUCUUCAACACUAAGAAGCCUAAAUUGAAUAAACACACACAAAACAUUGUUAAAAUUUUGCAAAAGUUUAUAAAAAAUUAUUUUUGUCACUAUUUAUUGAGAGACUGUUAACUAACCCAUAAUGUACUAAGUACUUUGUCCCAUGCUUCCAAGACACAUUAUAUUUAUGACCACAAUAAAAGAUGUGUAUAUUUUA